AGUGUCAGUGGUGUUGGCAUCAGCUUGGGCAGGUGUGCGGGCUCAGGAUGGGGCGGCCGUGGUGAGGAACCCUGGACUCUCAGAGAUGGAAUUUCACCGUGUUGCCUAGGCUGGUCUGGAGCUCUUGAUCUCAAGCGAUCCUCCCUGCCUCGGCCUCCCAACGUGCUGGGAUUAUAGGCGUGAGCCACCGCUCCUGGCCAGGGUCUGUUCCUAGUUGCAACAGUUCUUGGAAACCCACUCGAGAGGGCCACGCCUCCAUUCACCAGGCCACGGUGGGUGGUGUGCGUAUGUUUUGCUGAGGCCUGGUCAUCACGCUGUGGCUCCAAGGCUGGGACCAGCCACAGACCGAGAAGCCGGUCAGGUGCCAGCCAGAGAUUCAGGGCUCCCUCCCUCUGAACAUCCUGUCUUUAGCCCAUCCUUGGCAUCCCAGCUCAUGUCAUCCCAGCCACCUGCAGCAGUGCCCUAGGGCCCCAUCCCUCUGCGGAUCAUGCUCUUGGGCCACCUCCUCCAAGAAGCCUUCCCUGACCUCCCUCCUCCCAGCUCCCACCACAGGCAGAAUCUGGGCUUGCAGUUGUUUCAGGAAUGGAAGCCCCAUUCCCAGCAUCACAAGAGGCAACACCAGGAGCCAACAUGAGCUCGGGGACUGAACUGCUGUGGCCCGGAGCAGCGCUGCUGGUGCUGUUGGGGGUGGCAGCCAGUCUGUGUGUGCGCUGCUCACGCCCAGGUGCAAAGAGGUCAGAGAAAAUCUACCAGCAGAGAAGUCUGCGUGAGGACCAACAGAGCUUUACGGGGUCCCGGACCUACUCCUUGGUCGGGCAGGCAUGGCCAGGACCCCUGGCGGACAUGGCACCCACAAGGAAGGACAAGCUGUUGCAAUUCUACCCCAGCCUGGAGGAUCCAGCAUCUUCCAGGUACCAGAACUUCAGCAAAGGAAGCAGACACGGGUCGGAGGAAGCCUACAUAGACCCCAUUGCCAUGGAGUAUUACAACUGGGGGCGGUUCUCGAAGCCCCCAGAAGAUGAUGAUGCCAAUUCCUACGAGAAUGUGCUCAUUUGCAAGCAGAAAACCACAGAGACAGGUGCCCAGCAGGAGGGCAUAGGUGGCCUCUGCAGAGGGGACCUCAGCCUGUCACUGGCCCUGAAGACUGGCCCCACUUCUGGUCUCUGUCCCUCUGCCUCCCCGGAAGAAGAUGAGGAAUCUGAGGAUUAUCAGAACUCAGCAUCCAUCCAUCAGUGGCGCGAGUCCAGGAAGGUCAUGGGGCAACUCCAGAGAGAAGCAUCCCCUGGCCCGGUGGGAAGCCCAGACGAGGAGGACGGGGAACCGGAUUACGUGAAUGGGGAGGUGGCAGCCACAGAAGCCUAGGGCAGACCAAGAAGAAAGGAGCCAAGGCAAAGAGGGACCACUGUGCUCAUGGACCCAUCGCUGCCUUCCAAGGACCAUUUCCCAGAGCUACUCAACUUUUAAGCCCCUGCCAUGGUUGCUCCUGGAAGGAGAACCAGCCACCCUGAGGACCACCUGGCCAUGCGUGCACAGCCUGGGAAAAGACAGUUACUCACGGGAGCUGCAGGCCCGUCACCAAGCCCUCUCCCGACCCAGGCUUUGUGGGGCAGGCACCUGGUACCAAGGGUAACCCGGCUCCUGGUAUGGACGGAUGCGCAGGAUUUAGGAUAAGCUGUCACCCAGUCCCCAUAACAAAACCACUGUCCAACACUGGUAUCUGUGUUCUUUUGUGCUAUGAAUUUGGAUUCCUAAUUGCUAUUGUUGGUUGCUGGGGUUUUAAAUGAUUGAUAAGCUUGUACAGUUAACUUAUAGAGGGGGAGCCAUAUUUAACAUUCUGGAUUUCAGAGUAGAGAUUUCUGUGUUGUCUCCUAGAAAGCAUUACAUGUAGUUUAUUUCAGCAUCCUUGUUGGGUGGGGCCCUGGCUCUCUUCCCCUUUGGUGGGACCUCCCCUUUCUUUGGGCUUCAGUUCACUCAGGAAGAAAUGAGGCUGUCGCCAUCUUUAUGUGCUUCCAGUGGAAAUGUCACUUGCUACAGACAAUAGUGCAUGAGAGUCUAGAGAAGUAGUGACCAGAACAGGGCAGAGUAGGUCCCCUCCAUGGCCCUGAAUCCUCCUCUGCUCCAGGGCUGGCCUCUGCAGAGCUGAUUAAACAGUGUUGUGACUGUCUCAUGGGAAGAGCUGGGGCCCAGAGGGACCUUGAGUCAGAAAUGUUGCCAGAAAAAGUAUCUCCUCCAACCAAAACAUCUCAAUAAAACCAUUUUAGUUGAAAAGCA